AGUUCAGUCUUUGAUUGGUUGCUGAGAGGCGGGGCUACUCGACUGCUCUGGAGGUAGCGGCCGCGGUGAGGAGAGCCAUGGGACGGGCAGUCAAGGUUUUACAGCUCUUUAAAACACUGCACAGGACCAGACAACAAGUUUUUAAAAAUGAUGCCAGAGCAUUAGAAGCAGCCAGAAUAAAGAUAAAUGAAGAAUUCAAAAAUAAUAAAAGUGAAACUUCUUCUAAGAAAAUAGAAGAGCUAAUGAAAAUAGGUUCUGAUGUUGAAUUAUUACUCAGAACAUCUGUUAUACAAGGUAUUCACACAGACCACAAUACACUGAAACUGGUCCCUAGGAAAGACCUUCUUGUAGAAAAUGUGCCAUAUUGUGAUGCACCAACUCAGAAGCAAUGAGUUUUCUAGAAUACAACAAGUCUUUGUACUUUUUAACUUUAAAAUCUACAACUCUGGCAAAAGUCCUGGAAAUGCAGACAUUUUCCCUGAACUGGCAUAUUGAAAAUGAAUGAAUUACAGAAUAGCUUCAUAUUUAAAUUUCAUGUUAAAAGGUCAUUACUGAGAACUAAAGAACAUAAUUAAGUAUUUCUAAAGGAAAUUAGAUAAGAAAACAUUUCAUUUUCAUUGAAAAUCAAAUUUCAUAAAGCAAAGUAAAUGCUUAGGGAGAUAUAUUCAAUCUUUGACCUUGAUGAGUAUUUGAUCUUACCAUAGCUAUUUGAGAAUGUGGUGCUUUUACAAAUUGGUGAGUUUUCCUGCCAUGUGAAAUGCAAUUAUUACAUUUAAAUUGUUAGAUUAAAAUGAUAUUUAGUCCUGAAAAAUAUUAAAUUGGUCAAAAAAAUCACAGUGUAUGCCAGCUCUCUACAGAAAGUGGCCUUUGUUUUCUAAAGCACUGGGAUUAUUUCUGUAGCUAAUAUAUAAUUGUACAGUUUCUUUUUAGAGAUAGAGAGUAUCUCUGUGUUCUUAUGAAGACAUUUUUUAUCAGUUUUCUGAAAAUAGAUGAAUAAAAUAUUAUAGUCACCUAGGGUCACUAUGGAAUAAAGAAAUCCUAGUUUAAAGAGGAAAUAGUGGCCCUUGAUCAAACUAUUUAAUAUGGCCUUAGUAGAAUUAGCUGUAUUUAGACAAAGUUAGACUUUAGUGUGAAAUGUAAUCGGUGGCUACAUUCUCAUCGUUUUAAUUAAUGAAACUUAAAUGGCUUCUCUUCUUCCACAUGUCCUGUCCUUGACAAGAUGGGCAGUAUCACAAAAGGUCCUGGCAUUCUACCAUCUAACACUAGGAACUGUAAAAUACUGUUUAAUAUUCUUCUUGUUUCUCUUUUAUCUGUGUAUCUUUGCCAUUCUAUUUUCUCAGUGAAUAGUAUGUUUUCUCCCAUUCACUGAUAAAUUCUCUCAUUUGAUGAUGAUACAGGGUUUUUAAUUUUUGCAAGAUUCUCAAUGCAAGCAUUGUUAUGUAUCUAGAAAUUAUACCUAGAGAAAAAUGAAAGUCGUUUCAAAUUUGAAAUUUGCCCUUUUAAGAGAAUGCUGAAUGUCAUCGCAGUAUAUAAUCACUAUAUAAAUGUGCUGACUUACAGUUAUUUUAGUGUCUAUAUGACAUAUUUUGAGGAAAGUUGGCUGACGUUAUUUAAAUUUAAUAUAUAUUCUAUAUUUUAGUGUUAUUGAAUAUUUUAUCACUGAGCUUUUUUCUUUAACCUGAAUUCCCUGUUCCAUUUUUCAUUCAUAUUAAUUUAAAUAACUCCAGAUUUCUUUCUUAUAGUCAUUAUUAGUAGCAGAUGAGAUUAAUAAUUCACAUGUUUAUUAAAGAUAGUGGCUUAGAAAUUUUAAGAUAUAUUGAUAUAGGCCCGGGCGCUGUGGCUCACACCUGUAAUCCCGCACUUUGGGAGGCUGAGGCGGGCAGAUCACAAGGUCAGGAGUUCGAGACCAGCCUGGCCAAUGUGGUGAAACCCCAUCUCUACUAAAAACACAAAAAUUAGCCAGGUAUGGUGGCGGGCGCCUGUAGUCCCAGCUACUCGGGAGGCUGAGGCAGGAAAAUCACUUGAACCCGGGAGGUGGAGGUUGCAGUGAACUGAGAUUGUGCCACUGCACUCCAGCCUGGGGGACAGAGUGAGACUCUGUCUCAAAAAAAAAAAAGAAAAAAAAAGGAAAAAGGAAAAAAAAAAGAUAUAUUGAUACAGAUAGGUAGAUAUGAUAUUGUACUUUCAUGCCAUAAGACUACACAAUAAAGUUCCUGAAAGUUCCUGGCUGGGCGCAGUGGCUCACGCCUGUAAUCCCAGCACUUUGGGAGGCCGAGGCAGGCAGAUCACCUGAGGUCAGGAGUUCUAGACCAGCCUGACCAACAUGGGGAAACCCUGUCUCUACUAAAAAAAAUACAGAAUUAGCCAGGUGUGGUGGCACAUGUCUGUAAUCCCAGCUACUCGGGAGACUGAGGCAGGAGAAUUGCUUGAACCCAGGAGACGGAGGUUGCAGUGAGCCGAGAUCGCACCAUUGCACUCCAGCCUAGGCAACAAGAGUGAAACUCCGUCUCAAAAAUAAAUAAAUAAAUAAAGUUCCUGUGAAGUAUAUAAACAUGUCAACAACAGGCUUGACUGUCACAAAAUUCUGAAAGAUGUCGCACUCUAUUCUUAUAUAGCAUAUGCUAAUUUAUUUAUUUAUUUUUUGAGAUUGAGUUCUGCUGUGUCACCCAGGUUGGAGUGCAGUGGCAUGGUCAUGGUCCACUAAAGCCUUGACCCCUGGGGCUCAGCAGUUAUGCCAACUAAGCCUCCCAAAUAGCUGAGACUAGAGGUAUGCGCCACCACACCUAGCUAUUUUUUUUAUUUUUAGUAAGGACAAGGUCUCAUUAUGUUGGCCAGGCUGGUCUCAAAUUCCUGAGCUCAGUUGAUCCUCCCACCUCAGCCUCCCAAAGUGCUGGGAUUACAGGUGUAAGCCACUGCACCCUGCCUAUUCUUAUAAUCAUAUAUUUAUAUUUCAAAUGGAUUUUAACUGGUUAUUUAAUAGUUUAAUUAGAUAAAGUAAUUCAUGGCUGGGUGUGGUGGCUCACGCCUGUAAUCCCAGCACUUUGGCAGGCUGAGGCAGGUGGAUUACCUGAGGUCGGAAGUUCGAGACCAGCCCAACCAACGUGGAGAAACCCCAUCUCUAUUAAAAAUGCAAAAUUAGCAGGACAUGGUGAUACACACCUGUAAUCCCAGCUAGUCAGGAGGCUGAGGCAGGAGAAUUACUUGAGCCAGGGAAGCAGAGGUUGUGGUGAGCUAAGAUUGUGCCACUGCACUCCAGCCUGAGAGAACAAGACUCCGUCUCAAAAAAAGAAAAAAAGAAAACUUUUUUACACAUGGGUAUCUCACCAUGUUGCCCAGGCUGGAGUGCAGUAGCUAUUCAUAGGCACAGUCAUAGCACACUGCAGCCUAGAAUUUCUGACCUCAAGCAAUCAUCCUGCCUCAGCCUCCUAAGUAGCUAGGACUACAGGUGCAUACCACCAUAACCAGCUUUAAUUAAAUGUUUUUUAUUUGGUUAUUUUUUUUAAGUUUUCUGUAUUCACACAAGGGGUUGCCCAAAUAUAAUUUUGCUUUGACUAUUGAGAUCUAGUGAAAGUGGGGUAUAUGAAUUCUAAUUGCAAAUAUCCAGGCUCAGAGGCCCAGCAGGACUUUCUAACACAAUCUUUUAGCGGAAGUUAGAAAUGGUAUAUAGCAGGAGAGUCAGAUUUGAGAAGCAUAUGUAGAUUCGAAGCUGGGGGAAUAUGGCAGGUAGUUUGUACAACAUCUAAUUCAGAACAUUAAAAUUAAGAUUUUAGUCAAACUGUGUUUAAGUUAGUUCUUAUUUUCCUGUAGAUGCAUCUCACAGCAUCAGUACAAUACCAAAAAAGCACACAAGAAUAAGAAUAUGUGGAAUUUCUAUACCUAUUGACAAAGCACAUAAUUUAACCAUAAACACAAAGCCAUAGGUCAACAAAGAAAUGAAGAUUCCAGUUCUGAAGGUGAGUUUUCUGAAGCCAAAGUGGAUACAUGCAAAAUUAAUAUAGUUUUACUGUAUAUCAGUUGUCACCAAUCAGAAAUGGAAAACAGAUCCUAUUUAUAAUUGCAAACAAAACUGUAAAAUAGACUUUUUAAAGUCUGGGAAUAGACUUCUAAAAUAAGCUAUAACACUUAAAAAGGAGAGAUAUACUAUGUUCCUAGAUAGGACAAUUGAAAAUUCUGGAGAUGACAGUUUUUCAAAAAUCUAUUGAGGCCAGGUGCAGUGGCCCAUGCCUGUAGUUCCAGUACUUUGGGAGGCCUAGGUGGGUGGAUCACCUGAGGUUGGGAGUUUGAGACCAGCCUGACCAACAUGGAGAAACCCCGUCUCUACUAAAAAUACAAAAUUAGCCAGGCGUGGUGGUGCAUGCCUGUAAUCCCAGCUACUCGGGAGGCUGAGGCGUGAGAAUCGCUUGAACCCGGUAGGCAGAUGUUGCAGUGAGCCGAGAUCGCACCAUUGCACUCCAGCCUAGGCAACAAGAGCGAAACUCCAUCUCAAAAAUAGAAAAAACAUUUAUCGAAAUCCCAACAAGUUGACAAAUAUAUCCACAUAAAAAUAUAAAACUUCUGUAUUCUGUGAAAGCUACUAUAAAUAAAGUUUAGAGAAAGUUAUUUGCCACCUAUGUCAUGAUUGAAAUAGUUAAUUGAUCCUGUGAAUCAGUUAGCAAAACAUAACUCAAUGGAAAGAUAGGCAAAUGAUACAAAUAAGAAAUUCACAAAAGAAGAAAUACUAAGUCUCUAGUGAUGAGAGAAAUGUAAAUUAAAAUGAAACAUGUUUGUUCAUCAAGUUGUCACAAGUUAGACAAUCAUAUCCAAUAUUUUUAAAGGUUGUAAGACUAUAAGGAAAUAGCCACUGUCAUAUCAUUUUUAAAGGAAUAUAAAUUAUAGGGCCUUUUGUUUCUUUGGGUUUUUUUUUUUUAGAGACAAGAUCUCUCCGUGUUGUCUAGGCUGGACUCAAACUUCUGGACUCAAGCAAUCCUCGCAACAUCAUUAAUAGCUGAGAGUAGAGACUUGAGCCACCACACCUGACUAUAGGGCCUUUUUGAAAGGAAAAUUGACAUCAUCAAAAUUUUAAAUAUAUUCAGUCUAUUUCUCAAAAACUCAAAGAAUACUAAUAAAUGUGUACUCAGGUAUAUGUACAGAAAUUGCUGUAACAUUAUAAUUUUAAACAAUUUAAAACAGACUGAGUUUCCAAAGUUAGGGUACAAUGAAAGAAAAGGUGGCUUAUUUAUACUCUGGAAUAUUUUCCAAGAGUUGAAAAGGAUGAGGAUACACACACACACACACACACACACACACACACACACACACACACACAGUUUGGGUAUCCCUAAUCCAGAAAUUCAAAUGCUCCAAAGUCCAAAACUUUCUGACCCACCAACAUGACUGAUGCUCAAAGGAAAUGGCCACUGGAAGAUUUCAGAUUUUCAGAUUUGGAGUGCUCAACCAGUAAGUAUAUAAUGCAAAUAAUCCAAAAUACAAAAAAAAAAAAAAAGAAAUCUGAAACACUUCUGAUCCCAAGCAUUUCAGAAAACGGAUGUUCAUUUGUGUGUGUGUGUGUGUGUAAGCAGGUGUUGCUAGAAAUUCACUUAUAUACAAGAAAACUUUUUGUGUACAUAUUUGCAUAUAUAUGUACAAAUGGGUAGAAACGAUACAUGAUUAAUCUUAAUCGGGAAGGAAAAGAGAUUUAGGGAAGGAAGCAGUAAGUGAGAACUUUUAUUCUAUUUACUCCUGCACGUUUAAAUAUUGUUUACAGUGAGUAUAUCAACAUGUAAGUGUUAAAAGACAAUAAGCUACUAGUGAUUUUUAAUAUAAAAUUAACUAUAAAAUAUUUUAAAUAUUAGCAAAUAAUAUAGCACACUCAUGAACCUAAUUCCCACAUUUGAUAGUUGUUACAUUUUGCCAUGUUUGUUUAAAGGUCUAAGUCAUAAAAUCUUAUAAAGCUAAACCCCACCCUUCUCUUUCUCCUCUCUCUCCAGGAUAAUUACUGUUUUAUAGUUUGUGGAUAUCAUUCCCUUACUUGUGUUUAUACUUUUACCAAGUGUGUAUGUAUUCAAAAAACAGUUGUUUUGUGAUUUUAAAAUGUAAAUGAAUGGCGUUAUGCUCCAUGUAUUCUGCAACUUUUCAUCAUACAUUAGGUUUUGGCGAUUUAGCCAUAAUUUGGCAUGAAUUCAGGUCUUUUAAGUUUUAUUCCAUUGUAAGAAUAAACAAGUUUGUUCAUUCAUGUCUCCA